GCCAGCUGCGCUCUGAGUUCUGGGCCAGCUCCCCAGAGGCCUAGGCGCCGCCGCCGCGAGGGCGCGGGGCAGACAAAGGAGGCAGACAAAGGCGGGCGCAGCCCAGCAGCCGUGCGGGCACCGGGCGAGGCAGGCCCACUCCUCCCGGUAGCGGGAAGGAUGACCACGCUCACACGACAAGACCUCAACUUUGGCCAAGUGGUGGCCGAUGUGCUCUGCGAGUUCCUGGAGGUGGCUGUGCAUCUCAUCCUCUACGUGCGCGAGGUCUACCCCGUGGGCAUCUUCCAGAAACGCAAGAAGUACAACGUGCCGGUCCAGAUGUCCUGCCACCCGGAGCUGAAUCAGUAUAUCCAGGACACGCUGCACUGCGUCAAGCCACUCCUGGAGAAGAAUGAUGUGGAGAAAGUGGUGGUGGUGAUUUUGGAUAAAGAGCACCGCCCAGUGGAGAAAUUCGUCUUUGAGAUCACCCAGCCUCCACUGCUGUCCAUCAGCUCAGACUCGCUGUUGUCUCAUGUGGAGCAGCUGCUCCGGGCCUUCAUCCUGAAGAUCAGCGUGUGCGAUGCCGUCCUGGACCACAACCCCCCAGGCUGUACCUUCACAGUCCUGGUGCACACGAGAGAAGCCGCCACUCGCAACAUGGAGAAGAUCCAGGUCAUCAAGGAUUUCCCCUGGAUCCUGGCGGAUGAGCAGGAUGUCCACAUGCAUGACCCCCGGCUGAUACCACUAAAAACCAUGACGUCGGACAUUUUAAAGAUGCAGCUUUACGUGGAAGAGCGCGCUCAUAAAGGCAGCUGAGGGGGCACCUGCCACCCCACUGAUGCCCAAACUGUCAGACUUUGGGGGAUCCCCGCCUAGGGCAGUGCUGCAUGGCUGCCCUGAUUCCAAGUGCUCUUAUCGCCUCUGUGUGUGGAUCGCCCGCCCCAGCCCGGGGCCGCUCAGGUCUGCUUGGAGGAUGCCUCCCCCAGGAGGGCAGUGAGGGAUGCCGCAACCUCGACUUCUCAGCCUCCUGGGGUUCCGCCGGCCAACACUGUCUGUCUCAAAUACUGUGCUGUGAGUUGUUUCAAUAAAGGGGCCCCAAGGGCUGGGCUGA